ACCCUGCAAGCUGCAUCAGGCUUUAUCCUACUUGUUCCUUUGGUGAACCAGGUUCACUUAAACUUGCAAAAAGAUGACCGACCUCUUGAGAAGUGUUGUCACCGUAAUUGAUGUUUUCUACAAAUACACCAAGCAAGAUGGGGAGUGUGGCACACUGAGCAAGGGUGAACUAAAGGAACUUCUGGAGAAAGAGCUUCAUCCAGUUCUGAAGAACCCAGAUGAUCCAGACACAGUGGAUGUCAUCAUGCAUAUGCUGGAUCGAGAUCAUGACAGAAGAUUGGACUUUACUGAGUUUCUUUUGAUGAUAUUCAAGCUGACUAUGGCCUGCAACAAGGUCCUCAGCAAAGAAUACUGCAAAGCUUCAGGGUCAAAGAAGCAUAGGCGUGGUCACCGACACCAAGAAGAAGAAAGUGAAACAGAAGAGGAUGAAGAGGAUACACCAGGACAUAAAUCAGGUUACAGACAUUCAAGUUGGAGUGAGGGAGAGGAGCAUGGAUAUAGUUCUGGGCACUCAAGGGGAACUGUGAAAUGUAGACAUGGGUCCAACUCCAGGAGGCUAGGAAGACAAGGUAAUUUAUCCAGCUCUGGGAACCAAGAGGGAUCUCAGAAAAGAUACCACAGGUCCAGCUGUGGUCAUUCAUGGAGUGGUGGCAAAGACAGACAUGGUUCCAGCUCUGUAGAACUGAGAGAAAGAAUAAACAAGUCACACAUUAGCCCUUCUAGGGAAUCUGGGGAGGAGUAUGAAUCUGGAUCUGGAUCAAACAGUUGGGAAAGGAAAGGUCAUGGUGGUCUGUCAUGUGGAUUGGAGACUAGUGGGCAUGAAUCAAACUCUACUCAGUCAAGAAUUAGAGAACAAAAGCUUGGGUCUAGCUGUUCAGGUUCAGGAGACAGUGGGAGGCGAAGUCAUGCAUGUGGUUAUAGCAAUUCAAGUGGGUGUGGAAGGCCACAAAAUGCUUCAAGUUCUUGUCAGUCACAUAGAUUUGGAGGGCAAGGAAAUCAAUUUAGCUAUAUUCAGUCAGGCUGUCAGUCAGGAAUUAAGGGAGGACAAGGCCAUGGCUGUGUCUCAGGAGGUCAGCCCUCUGGAUGUGGUCAACCUGAGUCUAACCCCUGUAGUCAGUCCUAUAGUCAGAGAGGAUAUGGAGCUAGAGAAAAUGGUCAACCACAGAACUGUGGAGGACAAUGGAGAACAGGCUCAAGUCAGUCCUCUUGCUGUGGACAAUAUGGGUCUGGAGGUAGCCAGUCUUGUAGUAAUGGUCAACAUGAAUAUGGUUCCUGUGGCCGCUUUUCAAACUCUUCUAGUUCAAAUGAAUUUUCCAAAUGUGAUCAAUAUGGGUCUGGUUCAAGUCAGUCUACUAGCUUUGAACAACAUGGAACAGGCUUGAGUCAGUCCUCUGGGUUCGAACAACAUGUAUGUGGCUCAGGUCAAACUUGUGGCCAGCAUGAGUCUACAUCAAGUCAAUCCUUGGGCUAUGACCAGCAUGGGUCUAGCUCAGGUAAGACAUCUGGCUUUGGACAACAUGGGUCUGGCUCAGGUCAGUCCUCUGGCUUUGGACAAUGUGGGUCAGGCUCAGGUCAGUCCUCUGGCUUUGGACAGCAUGGGUCUGUCUCAGGACAAUCCUCUGGUUUUGGACAGCAUGGGUCUGUCUCAGGACAAUCCUCUGGUUUUGGACAACAUGAGUCUAGAUCACGUCAGUCUAGCUAUGGCCAACAUGGUUCUGGCUCAAGUCAAUCAUCUGGCUAUGGCCAAUAUGGGUCUAGAGAGACAUCUGGCUUUGGACAACAUGGGUUGGGCUCAGGUCAAUCCACUGGCUUUGGCCAAUAUGGAUCGGGCUCAGGUCAGUCCUCUGGCUUUGGACAACAUGGGUCUGGCUCAGGACAAUCCUCUGGCUUUGGACAACAUGAGUCUAGAUCAGGUCAGUCUAGUUAUGGCCAACACAGUUCUGGCUCAAGUCAGUCAUCUGGCUAUGGCCAACAUGGGUCUAGACAGACAUCUGGCUUUGGACAACAUGGGUCAGGCUCAAGUCAAUCCACUGGCUUUGGCCAAUAUGGAUCAGGCUCAGGUCAGUCCUCUGGCUUUGGACAACAUGUUUCUGGCUCAGGACAAUCCUCUGGUUUUGGACAACAUGAGUCUAGAUCAGGUCAUUCUAGCUAUGGCCAACAUGGUUUUGGCUCAAGUCAAUCAUCUGGCUAUGGUCAACAUGGGUCAAGUUCAGGACAGACAUCUGGAUUUGGACAACACGAGUUAAGCUCAGGUCAGUCUUCCAGCUUUGGCCAACAUGGAUCAGGCUCAGGUCAGUCCUCUGGCUUUGGACAACAUGGGUCUGGCUCAGGACAAUCCUCUGGCUUUGGACAACAUGAGUCUAGAUCAGGUCAGUCUAGCUAUGGCCAACACAGUUCUGGCUCAAGUCAGUCAUCUGGCUAUGGCCAACAUGGGUCUAGACAGACAUCUGGCUUUGGACAACAUGGGUCAGGCUCAAGUCAAUCCACUGGCUUUGGCCAAUAUGGAUCAGGCUCAGGUCAGUCCGCUGGCUUUGGACAACAUGGGUCUGGCUCAGGACAAUCCUCUGGCUUUGGACAGCAUGAGUCUAGAUCACAUCAGUCCAGCUAUGGCCAACAUGGUUCUGGCUCAAGUCAAUCAUCUGGCUAUGGUCAACAUGGGUCAAGUUCGGGACAGACAUCUGGCUUUGGACAACACAGGUCAAGCUCAGGUCAAUACUCUGGCUUUGGACAACAUGGAUCAGGCUCAGGUCAGUCCAGUGGCUUUGGACAACAUGGGACUGGCUCAGGACAAUACUCUGGUUUUGGACAACAUGAGUCUAGAUCACAUCAGUCUAGCUAUGGCCAACAUGGUUCUGGCUCAAGUCAGUCAUCUGGCUAUGGUCAACAUGGGUCAAGUUCAGGACAGACUUUUGGAUUUGGACAACACAGGUCAGGCUCAGGUCAAUCCUCUGGCUUUGGCCAACAUGGAUCAGGCUCAGGUCAGUCCUCUGGCUUUGGACAACAUGAGUCAGGCUCAGGAAAAUCCUCUGGCUUUGGACAGCAUGAGUCUAGAUCAAGUCAGUCUAAUUAUGGCCAACAUGGUUCUGGCUCAAGUCAGUCAUCUGGCUAUGGUCAACAUGGGUCUAGUUCAGGACAGACAACUGGCUUUGGACAACACAGGUCAAGCUCAGGCCAAUACUCAGGCUUUGGACAACAUGGAUCAGGCUCAGAUCAGUCCUCUGGCUUUGGACAACAUGGGACUGGUUCAGGACAAUCCUCUGGUUUUGGACAAUAUGAGUCUAGAUCACGUCAGUCUAGCUAUGGCCAACAUGGUUCUGGCUCAAGUCAAUCAUCUGGCUAUGGUCAACAUGGGUCAAAUUCAGGACAGACAUCUGGAUUUGGACAACACAGGCCAGGCUCAGGUCAGUCCUCUGGCUUUGGCCAAUAUGGAUCGGGCUCAGGUCAGUCUUCUGGCUUUGGACAACAUGGGUCAGGCACAGGUAAAUCCUCUGGCUUUGCACAGCAUGAGUACAGAUCAGGUCAGUCUAGCUAUGGCCAACAUGGUACUGGCUCCAGUCAAUCAUCUGGCUGUGGCCAACAUGAGUCUGGCUCAGGUCCAACCACAAGUUUUGGACAGCAUGUGUCUGGCUCAGACAAUUUCUCUAGUUCUGGACAACAUAUAUCUGACUCAGGUCAGUCCACUGGAUUUGGCCAAUAUGGUUCAGGCUCAGGUCAAUCAACUGGCUUGGGCCAGGGUGAAUCUCAACAAGUAGAGUCAGGAUCCACAGUUCAUGGGAGACAGGAAACUACUCAUGGUCAGACAAUAAAUACCACUAGACAUAGCCAGUCUGGUCAAGGACAAUCCACACAGACAGGGUCCAGGGUAACUAGAAGACGAAGAUCUAGCCAAAGUGAGAACAGUGACAGUGAAGUGCACUCAAAGGUCUCACACAGACAUUCAGAACACAUUCACACACAAGCUGGAUCUCACUACCCAAAGUCAGGAUCCACAGUUCGCAGAAGACAAGGAACUACUCAUGGACAGAGAGGAGAUACCACUAGACAUGGCCAUUCUGGUCAUGGACAGUCUACACAGACAGGUUCCAGAACAUCUGGAAGACAGAGAUUUAGCCACAGUGAUGCCACUGACAGUGAAGUGCACUCAGGGGUCUCACAUAGACCACACUCACAAGAACAAACUCACAGCCAAGCUGGAUCUCAACAUGGAGAGUCAGAAUCCACAGUUCAUGAGAGACAUGAAACUACUUAUGGACAGACAGGAGAGGCCACUGGACAUGGCCACUCUGGUCAUGGACAGUCCACACAGAGAGGGUCCAGGACAACUGGAAGAAGGGGAUCUGGCCAUAGUGAGUCCAGUGACAGUGAAGUGCACUCAGGGGGCUCACACAGACCACAAUCACAAGAACAAACUCAUGGCCAAGCCGGAUCUCAACAUGGAGAGUCAGGAUCCACAGUUCAUGGGAGACACGGAACUACUCAUGGACAGACAGGAGAUACCACUAGACAUGCCCACUAUCAUCAUGGAAAAUCCACACAGAGAGGGUCCAGUACAACUGGAAGAAGGGGAUCUGGCCACAGUGAGUCCAGUGACAGUGAAGUGCACUCAGGGGGCUCGCACACACAUUCAGGACACACUCACGGCCAAAGUGGAUCUCAACAUGGAGAGUCAGAAUCCAUAAUUCAUGACAGACACAGAAUUACUCAUGGACAGACAGGAGAUACCACUAGACAUUCCUACUCUGGUCAUGAACAAACCACACAGACAGGGUCCAGGACAACUGGAAGACAGAGAACUAGCCACAGUGAGUCCACUGACAGUGAAGUGCACUCAGGGGGCUCACACAGACCACACUCACGAGAACACACUUACGGCCAAGCCGGAUCUCAACAUGAAGAGCCAGAAUUCACAGUUCAUGAGAGACACGGAACUACUCAUGGACAGAUAGGAGAUACCACUGGACAUUCCCACUCUGGUCAUGGACAGUCCACACAGAGAGGGUCCAGGACAACUGGAAGACAGAGAUCUAGCCACAGUGAGUCCAGUGACAGUGAAGUGCACUCAGGGGUCUCACACACACAUACAGGACACACUCAUGGUCAAGCUGGAUCUCAACAUGGACAGUCAGAAUCCAUAGUUCCUGAGAGACAUGGAACUACUCAUGGACAGACAGGAGAUACCACUAGACAUGCCCACUAUCAUCAUGGAUUAACCACACAGACAGGGUCCAGGACUACUGGAAGAAGGGGAUCUGGCCACAGUGAGUACAGUGACAGUGAAGGGUACUCAGGAGUCUCACAUACACAUUCAGGACACACUCAUGGCCAAGCCAGAUCUCAACAUGGAGAGUCAGAAUCCAUAGUUCAUGAGAGACAUGGAACUAUACAUGGACAGACAGGCGAUACCACCAGACAUGCCCACUCUGGUCAUGGACAGUCCACACAGACAGGGUCCAGGACCACUGGAAGAAGGUCAUCUGGCCACAGUGAGUACAGUGACAGUGAAGGGCACUCAGGGUUCUCACAAAGACCACACUCACGAGGACACACUCACGGCCAGGCUGGAUCUCAACAUGGAGAGUCAGAAUCCAUAGUUGACGAGAGACAUGGAACUACUCAUGGACAGACAGGAGAUACCAGUGGACAUUCUCAAUCUGGUCAUGGACAGUCCACACAGUCAGGAUCCAGUACAACUGGAAGAAGGAGAUCUGGCCACAGUGAGUCCAGUGACAGUGAAGUGCACUCAGGGGGCUCACAUACACAUUCAGGACACACACACAGCCAAGCCAGGUCUCAACAUGGAGAGUCAGAAUCCACAGUUCACAAGAGACACCAAACUACUCAUGGACAGACAGGAGAUACCACUGAACAUGGCCACCCUAGUCAUGGACAAACCAUACAGACAGGGUCCAGGACAACUGGAAGAAGGGGAUCUGGCCACAGUGAGUACAGUGACAGUGAAGGGCCCUCAGGGGUCUCACACACACAUUCAGGACACACUCACGGUCAAGCUGGAUCUCACUAUCCAGAGUCAGGAUCCUCAGUUCAUGAGAGACACGGAACUACUCAUGGACAAACAGCAGAUACCACUAGACAUGGCCACUCUGGUCAUGGACAGUCCACACAGAGAGGGUCCAGGACAACUGGAAGAAGGGCAUCUGGCCACAGUGAGUACAGUGACAGUGAAGGGCACUCAGGGGUCUCACACACACAUUCAGGACACGCUCAUGGCCAAGCCGGAUCUCAACAUGGAGAGUCAGGAUCCUCAGUUCAUGAGAGACACGGAACUACUCAUGGACAGACAGGAGAUACCACUAGACAUGCUCACUCUGGUCAUGGACAGUCCACACAGAGAGGGUCAAGGACAGCUGGAAGAAGGGGAUCUGGCCACAGUGAGUCCAGUGACAGUGAAGUGCACUCAGGGGUCUCACACACACAUUCAGGACACACUUAUGGCCAAGCCAGAUCUCAACAUGGAGAGUCAGGAUCUGCCAUUCACGGGAGACAGGGAACUAUACAUGGACAGACAGGAGAUACCACUAGACAUGGCCAGUCUGGUCAUGGACAGUCCACACAGACAGGUUCCAGGACAACUGGAAGACAAAGAUCUAGUCACAGUGAGUCCAGUGAUAGUGAAGUGCACUCAGAGGCCUCACCCACACAUUCAGGACACACUCACAGCCAAGCCGGAUCUCGACAUGGACAGUCAGGAUCCUCAGGUCAUGGGAGACAGGGAACUACUCAUGGACAGACAGGAGAUACCACUAGACAUGCCCACUAUGGUUAUGGACAAUCCACACAGAGAGGGUCCAGGACAACUGGAAGAAGGGGAUCUGGCCACAGUGAGUCCAGUGACAGUGAAGUGCACUCAUGGGGCUCACACACACAUUCAGGACACAUUCAGGGCCAAGCUGGAUCUCAACAAAGACAGCCAGGAUCCACAGUUCAUGGGAGACUGGAAACUACUCAUGGACAGACAGGAGAUACCACUAGACAUGGCCAUUCUGGUUAUGGACAAUCCACACAGACAGGUUCCAGAUCUAGUAGAGCAAGUCAUUUUCAGUCACAUAGUAGUGAAAGGCAAAGGCAUGGAUCAAGUCAGGUUUGGAAACAUGGCAGCUAUGGACCUGCAGAAUAUGACUAUGGGCACACUGGGUAUGGGCCUUCUGGUGGCAGCAGAAAAAGCAUCAGUAAUUCUCACCUUUCAUGGUCAACAGACAGCACUGCAAACAAGCAACUGUCUAGACAUUGACAGUUAUUUUCUAGUUCUGACCUUAUAGUAUCCAAAGCAACUAAAAGAACAGGAAGACACAGUUUAAAUCAUGAACAGUCAAUGGUAAGUUAUGAACAUUCAGUUGAUUCUCAGUAUCAGUCUCGACCUAUUAUUAUAAGAAGUCAGGAAUCUAGUCAUGGACAUUCUAUAGUAACUCAUAAACAGUCAAACAACACCUAUGUUCAACCUGGAUAUAACACAGCCAGAAGGGAGGGAUGUACACAUAGCCAGUCAAAUGACCACCUUGGAUUUGGCCAUGGACAAUCCAUAUCAGUUCAUGGCCAUUCAAAAUCUAGUUCAAUCAGAAAACAGGAAUCCCAUACUGAUAACAAAAAGCAUUCAGAAGAUUGGGAGAAAGACACUCAUGAGCAAUUAGGAUCUAGGCAUGGGAAGUUAGAGUUCAAUACAAUAGGUAUACAUGGAUCUAGCCAGCAACAUUUCGGAGAUACAACUUUUCAUGGGCAGGUAAGAUCCAGCACAGGUUUUGCCAGAUAGGUAUUAAGUCAUGGGCCAUCAAGAGAUGCCUAGGGUCAGUCUGGAUUCAGUACCAAUGAAAGACAAGUAUACAGCCAUGGCCAAUCAAAUGAUAGUUAUGAGUAGUCAAAUGACAGCAAAAGUCAAAGAUACAUUUUCAGUCACUUUCUUGACAGCCAAGACCCUGCAGGAAUUGAAGAGUAUAGGUAUAGAUAUUCAUCAAGCAGUGCAACCAUAUGCAGUGGGGGAGACAAAGGCAAGAGUCAGAGUCAAGUCUGUCAGGAGGUAUCAGAAUAUACGGUGAGGAUGUGGGCAAAAAACAAAGAGGCUCUGAGGCCAGCGGUUACCAUACAAAGGAAAGAACAGGCUCUGGUUCCUUCUGCUUAGAUAGCAACACCCCACUCUAUGAAUAUGUCCAAGAACAAAGGAGUUAUUACUUUGAAUAAGAAGCCAACAUAAACUAGCCCAAGAUAAGAACUAACCCAGAGAAGAAAUGAGACACAUACAUGAAAUUAAGGUAUUUAACAUGAUCUCCUCUUUUGGUAGUAAGGGUAUAUGUCUGUUCUUUCAUUUUAACUAUAGUUCUGUACUAUAUUACUUUUGUUUGGUGCCAGGUGUUUUUGUAAGGCUCCACAUUCAUUGAACUCCUUGGUUAGAAAAUAGUGAAUGAGGCCGGGCGCGGUGGCUCACGCCUGUAAUCCCAGCACUUUGGGAGGCCAAGAUGGGUGGAUCACGAAGUCAGGAGUUCGAGACCAGCCUGGCCAACAUAGUGAAAUCCCGUCUCUACUAAAAAUACAAAAAUUAGCUGGGUGCAGUAGCGGGCACCUGUAAUCCUAGCUACUCAGGAGGCUGAGGCAGGAGAAUUGGUUGAACCCGGGAGGCAGAGGUUGCAGUGAGCCGAGAUCGCACCACUGCACUCCAGCCUGGGUGACUGAGCAAGACUCCACCUUGAAAAAAAGAAAGAAAGAAAAUAGUGAAUGGAAGAAAAAGAUAAACACCAUUUGGGGCUAUAUUCAGAACUAUAUAAUAAAGAGAGAUUUGUGUGGUUGGGAAUAAAAUUAGGUUUUAAAAAAAUUUCCGAAUUUCAAAAUUUGGAUUUUCCAGAUUUUGUUUUAAUUAAUUAUUGACAAACCUAUCCAAGGAGCUAAAUGACGUGGUUUAGGAGCCAAAACGUCUCUAGAAACAUUAUAACACAUCCCAUCCUGAACAAAGAAUGUUGUCAUAGUUUCCCACAUGAAUAUUCAGAAUAUUUGCAUCUUUUUGUGUCACUACUGGAAUUCUGUACAAUUAUAUUUAAAUUUAUUGUCAUGGCCUUCUGGAUAUAGGAUCCAGAAAAUUGUACUUCAUAAAAAUUGGCAAUAAACAUUUCAUCAAGUUAUA